GCGUCGGGAGGCUCCGUGGCCGUCCCCGGGUUGAAGUUGGGAGUGCAGCCUUCAUUCUGAACCCAUUUAGGCAGCAUGGGCAGCCCUCCUCGCCAUGGGCAGGAUCAGAGCCCCCCCGCCCAGUCUGGGGGUUGCUCCUGGAUGCUGUCUGGGAGGCUUGCUCAUGGUGACAUCCUCAUCUCCCCGUCCACGUUACCGCAUUCAGAGCUUGGGUCACCUGGACACUGAACUCAGGCGGAAUUCUCCACGAGUUUUGAGCAGCCUCGGGUUUCCCACCACCUCCAAAUCAUGGAAGACACACGGUGCAGGCAGAGCCCCCCAGCCGUGGCCAGCCCUUCCGGCAGCUCCGAAGCCACUGGCAAGCCCCGAGGCAGGGAUGGCCGGCCCAGGAGGGAGGAGGACGACGUCCCUCCCGAAGAGAAGAGGCUGCGGCUGUAGCUGGAGGGGGGAAGCGCAGAACCCGAGGACUGCGAGGACGGGGAGGACGCGCCGCGGCCAGGCAGGGAGGAGACCGGCACCCAGACAGGUGGCGAAGGCAGAGGAGUGGUCAUUUUUCUUCUUGUGGCCUCUGGAAUGUGACACAGAACUCAAGGGACAGGAAGGAGAUGAGUUGGAGGCUGGGACAGGGGUCCCUGCCAGGGAUGCUGGUGACUCACGUGACAGUGUUGAUGUGUGGAGUCCGGUGCCUGGUUUGGGGAAUGUUCGUGGGAUAUGUUCCAAAGGACUGACAGACCUAUCAGGUACUGGAGGUGAAUGGUCAAGUCUGAUCUCAGGGCUGACAGUGUCAGGCAAGGACAGGAAGUUGGCAUUGGUCUCAUUGGCUGAGGUUGUUGGGACCCAGGGGGCAAUGUGUGCCAGGACAGAUGGGUCUGGGGCUAGGAAGGCAGGUUUGGGCUGGCGACCCGGGCAUGGGAGGCAUCCCAGGUAGACAGUGGUUGAGGCUGUGGAAAUGACCGCGAUUGCCUGGGAUGAGAGUGGAGACAGACAAGAUGGAGGUUUUGCUUUAAGCCUGGGGAGCCCACCUCCCAGGUUCAAGCGAUUCUCCUGCCUCAGCUUCCCAAGUAGCUGGGAAUGCAGGUGCGUACCACCA